GCCGUGAUCCUGCCCCUGCCCUGCAGCCUGGGUUAUACAGCGAGACAAAAGAAAAAAGAAAAAAGUUAGUGGUAACAGGAUAAACUACAUAGCCAUAUAGUAUUCCUUCACAUUCAUGAAGCAGGUCAAUUUGAAGCUUGAGGACGACUUCCAUUCCUCUAGGUGAAUCUACCAAGAAAUGCCUUGGUAGAGCUAGGAGUGCCAAUGGUAUCAGCAAGGCCAGCCUGCUUCCCUGUGAUUCAUGGUAAUUCUCACUAUGACUUUGACAUGAUGUUCCUACACUGUGCCUAUCAACACUUGUAGACACACUGUAUAAGCGUUUGUUACAUUUACUUUUUCUUUUGUCAUUACGUCUUUUAUUACAGAGGCCACUGUGCACUCCACAAUCACACACUUACACAGCUCUGCCUUGCCAAGCAGUGUAGACCCUGCCAAGCAGUGUAGACAGAUUCUGGAUAACUAUCUUUGCAUCCUUCCCCAUACCAUGUCCCCGAUGUUGAACUGAAGCAGCUCCUUCCACGUUCCCUACCCGUUAAUUAGCCAGGCCACUGCCCACAUUGUCACAAACAUUAUAUUAACUGAAAAACUGGCCCAUGCCAUAUUCCAUUAUGAGAAAUUAUUUUUAAUUUGAUUAAAUUCCAAUGUUUAUUCAGAAAACCUGGUAGAGAUUGAAUUGCUCUAUGUACCUUUCUUAGUUUUCUUCUUCUUAGCAUAUUUUGACCAUUUAUCUUCUACACCUGGCUGACCUGCAUGGUCCGUGUAGUGUAACUUCUACUUGGUGUUUGCGCUUUGCUUUGUUUUCAAAUUUAAAUUGUGAGAUACAUUUUUAAACCUAUCUAAGAAAUAGCCCUGAUAUUGAAAUGGCUUCUGUGGAAUAGGUUUGACAGAUGUAAGUCUUUGAUUCUUUGGCUUUGGUUUUUGUGCCUGUUACAGUUUUACACACAUUCAUUCAGAGGAAGACAUUACCAUCAGUGUGUGGUUUAUUUUUUCAAAUUCCAGUAUGUUUUUAAAGACCCAUAUUUCACUAAGCAGUGUACUUGUUGAAACCGAUGUGAGUGACUUUGUUUCCACAUGUGAUAGAGCAUCAGAUACUGGAGUUUGCCAGGGGUAGAAUGGUUGGAUUCAGGAAUGUUUAGCUGACUCAUAGCAGGAAGUUAUCCUGUAAAAAAAUGAAGCAAGGCAGGGAAGACAGAUUUAAGUACCAUGCAGCUCAAAACGACAAUUACAUUGUCAUUUUCGUUGUGAAUACUUCUAGGUUCUAUAUUGGCUGUGAUCUUUGUACUAACUGGUAUUAUGGAGAAUGUGUUGGCAUCGCAGAAAAGGAGGCUAAGAAAAUGGAUGUGUACAUCUGUAAUGAUUGUAAAUGGGCACAAGAGGACAGCAGUGAGGAAUUGUACUGUAUCUGCAGAACACCUUUCGGAUCUUGCAGAUUUUUUAUUGGCCAUGAUCGGUGUCAGAAUUGGUACCAUGGGUGCUGCAUUGGCAUCUUGCAGAGUGAGGCAGAGCUCAUUGAUGAGUAUGUCUGUCCACAGUGCCAGUCAACAGAGGAUGUCAUGACAGUGCUCACACCACUAACAGAGAAGGAUGAUGAGGAGUUGAAGAGGGUGCUCCGUUCCUUACAGAUGAGAGCCCAUAAGAUGGCCCGGCCUUUCCUUGAACCAGUAGACCCUAAUGAUGCACCAGAUUAUUAUGGUGUUAUUAAGGAACCUGUGGGUACACAUGAGUUGAAUUUGAAGUUUUUUCAGAAGUCUCAGUGUAUAUUUUAUUAACCAUAAAAUUAAUAUCUUAGAAUACUUUUAGCAAGGCUGCUGGGGGUAUAAAUUGGUAUGGUCACUUUGGAGGGUAAAUUGAUAGUAUCUAUUACAGUUGAAUUGUGCAUACUCGGUUAUUUUAUUUUAUUUUUUUGAGAUGGAGUCUCACCCUGUUGCCAGGCUGGAGUGCAGUGGUGU